AGACCAGUGAGCCUCCUGAUCCACCAAGACCAUAUGGUGUUUUUCAUAAAAGAGAGAGAUCAUUCCCUUGACUUUGGACUUCGCUUAUUGAACCCCUGGACAACGGAAUCUCCCUCUGUCGCCCAGGCUGGAGUGCAGUGGCACCAUCUCGGCUUACCGCAACCUCCGCCUCCUGGGUUCAAACAAUACUCCUACCUUGGCCUCCUGAGUAGCUGGGAUUACAGGAAUCAAGGUUGCUAAGAGACCACCUGUGCUGAAUACACUUUGUUCUGGCAAGAGCAGAAAACUGAGAAGCCGUGUUACCUACCACUACCUGGGAUUAAUUCAGGGAGCGGGAUAAUUCUGGAUAUGACUGGUAAAAACUGGAUAUUAAUUUCUACUACUACUCCCAAAAGUCUAGAAGAUGAAAUUGUGGGAAGACUUCUAAAAAUUUUGUUUGUUAUCUUUGUUGACUUAAUUUCUAUUAUAUAUGUUGUGAUAACUUCUUAGAAAGCUGACUUCCUUUCCAUGUACAUUUCAAACUGAAUUACAGUGAAUAAAAAUUUGUAUUUUAACUUGUUGAGUGACUCACAUUUUAUGACAUUGCCAAUUUAUUCUAGAAGCCAACAGGACACUGCAAUACAAACAACAUUGUGUAUUGUUUAGUUCUUUAUGGUUUAUGAAACAUUCACAUAUACUGAAGUGAAUUUUUUUCCCCAAAAACAUCUAUCCUACUGAGUCAUGAAACUUCUAGAUUUUUAGCCAGGUGUGGUGGCUCACACCUGUAAUCCCAGCACUUUGAGAGGCCCAGGUAGGCGGAUCCCUUGAGUGCAGGAGUUCGAUACGGGCCUGAGCAACCUGAAGAAAUCCCAUCUCUA